GGGAUUCUCAGCGUUCUCUGGUAGCGACCAUUUUGGUUAAUGUUGGGUGUGUUUCUGCGGUUUGUGAGGUGAGAGGCGCUGGAGCUAUGGGUCCGAACCGCGGUGUCUGAACCCAGAAGGUCACCUCAUCCUAACCCGAAUCCUGAAGCAGCGAGAGAGCGGCGACUGUUCACAGGUCUGCAGCCCGGACCCGGCGUCGGGACACUGAGGCGUUCGCGGGAGAGGUCCUUGUUUCUGACACCUGUGGGAUGCGGUGGGGAGAGCGACAGGCACAGGGACCGGCGCGGGCUAUGGCCUGGAGGACAGACCCGGGAGGAUGGAACCUGGGGUCCACAGGCGCCUGUAGGGAACAACGUGUGAGGCGAAGCUUCUCCUGGAAGAGCAGGCUGGGGGCUGUGUAUUCGCUGUGAAGACGCUAGAAGCCAUGGAGAGUUUCGAAGAAAGGAGGGAUGCGAUCCAAGUCCAGGCUUUUAAGGUUUCCCAAAGGCCAAAGGAAGAACAUAGUAGAGGAGAUGAGGACCUUAGGGUUCUGGGAGGUUGACUCCUUUGUUGAUAGAUCACAUAGGUGGUAGAGAUGACAUUUUGCACUGAGACACGCAGGUCAACCAGUCUGAGGUCACCUGGCUCCAGCGAUAAGAAAAGGUUCAAGGAGACCUGAGCUUAUCAGAUCCCCUUUGUAACGUCUGCUUUCCCCUCAGACACUCCUGGCUACAAAAGCACGUAAAGAACCCACUGAGGGGGUCGGGCAAGGUGGCUCCCACCUGUAAUCCCAGCACUUUGGGAGGCCGAGGCGGGCGGAUCACCUGAGGUCGGGAGUUCGAGACCAGCCUGACCAACAUGGAGAAACCCCGUCUCUAACAAAAAUACAAAAUUAGCCAGGCGUGGUGAUGCCGCAUGACUGUAAUCCCAGCUACUCAGAGGCUAAGGCAGGAGAAUUGCUUGAACUCGGGAGGCAGAGGUUGCGGUGAGCCAUUGCACUCCGGCCUGGGCAACAAGAGCGAAACUCUGGCUCAAAAAAAGGAACCCACAGAGGGAAUUAGAGGGUGUUCCAUUCCCUCACUGGCCUUAUUCCCCAUUCACAUGUUCUCUAGCUUGUGAUGUCCUGGGACUCUUACUUGCCAUUUUUUCAGUCCUUUGAUCUGAGAACACUGGAGAAACCCUAAACCCAGAAUCCUAAGUCCAUGACACAGGAUGUAUGGAGGCAUCAUCUGGCUGCAAAGAAGAGAACACACUGUGUUUGAGGGAGGAGGAAGGAGGAUCAGAGUUUAAACUCCUGCCAUAAUGCAGGGCACUGUGGCAUUUGAAGAUGUGGCUGUGAACUUUUCCCAGGAGGAGUGGAGUCUCCUUAGUGAGGUUCAGAGAUGCCUUUACCAUGACGUGAUGCUGGAGAACUGGGUACUUAUAUCCUCCCUGGGUUGUUGGUGUGGAUCAGAAGAUGAGGAGGCACCUUCUAAGAAGAGCAUUUCUAUACAAAGAGUGUCUCAGGUCAGCACUCCUGGGGCAGGUGUGUCUCCCAAGAAGGCCCACUCUUGUGAAAUGUGUGGCGCGAUCUUGGGAGACAUUUUGCACUUGGCAGAUCAUCAGGGGACACAUCACAAGCAGAAACUGCACAGGUGUGAGGCAUGGGGGAAUAAAUUGUAUGAUAGUUCAAACCGUCCGCACCAGAAUCAGUACCUUGGAGAGAAACCCUAUAGAAGCAGUGUUGAGGAAGCAUUGUUUGUGAAGAGGUGUAAGUUCCAUGUGUCAGAGGAGUCAUCUAUCUUCAUUCAGAGUGGAAAGGACUUUUUGCCCAGCUCAGGAUUACUGCUGCAGGAGGCCACUCACACUGGGGAGAAGUCAAACAGCAAACCUGAGUGUGAGUCUCCCUUUCAGUGGGGAGAUACUCAUUACAGCUGUGGAGAAUGCAUGAAACAUUCUAGCACCAAACACGUAUUUGUUCAACAGCAGAGACUUCCCUCUAGAGAGGAAUGUUAUUGCUGGGAAUGUGGGAAAUCCUUUAGCAAAUAUGAUAGCGUCAGUAAUCAUCAGAGAGUUCACACUGGGAAAAGACCUUAUGAAUGUGGAGAAUGUGGGAAAUCUUUUAGUCAUAAGGGCAGCCUUGUUCAGCAUCAGCGAGUUCACACUGGGAAAAGACCUUAUGAAUGUGGAGAAUGUGGGAAAUCUUUUAGUCAUAAGGGCAGCCUUGUUCAGCAUCAGCGAGUUCAUACUGGAGAAAGACCUUAUGAGUGUGGAGAAUGUGGGAAAUCUUUUAGUCAAAAUGGUACUCUCAUUAAACAUCAACGAGUUCACACUGGAGAAAGACCUUAUGAGUGUGAAGAAUGUGGGAAAUGUUUUACUCAGAAGGGCAAUCUCAUUCAACAUCAACGAGGUCACACUAGUGAAAGACCUUAUGAGUGUGAAGAAUGUGGAAAAUGUUUUAGUCAAAAGGGCACCCUAACUGAACAUCAUCGAGUUCACACUAGAGAACGACCUUAUGAGUGUGGAGAAUGUGGGAAAUCUUUUAGUCGAAAGGGACACCUUAGGAACCAUCAGCGAGGUCACACUGGAGAAAGACCUUACGAGUGUGGAGAAUGUGGGAAAUCUUUUAGUCGAAAGGGCAACCUCAUUCAGCAUCAGCGAAGCCACACUGGAGAAAGGCCUUAUGAGUGUAGAGAGUGUAGGAAAUUAUUUAGGGGCAAGUCCCACCUCAUUGAACACCAGAGAGUUCACACUGGAGAAAGGCCAUAUGAAUGUAAUGAAUGUGGGAAAUCAUUUCAAGACAGCUCUGGGUUUCGUGUUCAUCAGAGAGUUCACACUGGAGAAAAACCGUUUGAGUGUAGUGAAUGUGGGAAGUCAUUUCCUCAAAGCUGUUCCCUCCUUCGACAUCGGAGAGUUCAUACUGGAGAAAGGCCUUAUGAAUGUGGAGAAUGUGGAAAGUCAUUUCAUCAGAGCUCUUCCCUCCUUCGACAUCAGAAAACUCACACUGCAGAAAGACCUUAUGAGUGCAGAGAAUGUGGGAAAUUCUUCUCCAGUCUCCUUGAACACAGGAGAGUUCACACUGGAGAAAGGCCUUAUGAAUGCAGGGAAUGUGGAAAAACAUUUACUCGAAGGUCUGCGCAUUUUAAACAUCAGAGACUUCAUACUCGAGGAAAGCCUUACGAGUGCAGCGAAUGUGGGAAAUCCUUUGCUGAAACCUUCAGUCUUACUGAACACAGGAGAGUACACACUGGAGAAAGGCCUUAUGAGUGCAGUGAAUGUGGAAAAUCAUUUCAUCGAAGCUCUUCUCUCCUUCGACAUCAGAGAGUUCACACAGAAAGAAGUCCUUACAAGUGAAAAGAAAUUUGGGAAAUUCUUUAGCUAAACCUCUGUGCAUCUUCUUGAUCAGAGGGUUCUUACUGGAUCAGGACCUUAUGAGUGUGACAAACGUGGGAUAUUCUUUAUGCAGAAGUCUUGUUUUAUUACAUACAGAAGAGCUCCCACUGCAGAAGGGCCUCUUGAGUGCGAUGAAUGUGAGAAAGCCUUCUGCCUUCUGUCAUUGGAUAACAGAUUGUUCUCAUAAGGAAAACACUGUACACGUACAGGAAAUAUUAUUUCUUGUAAAACAUAACACUGGAGGAGAUGCCUUAUGACGGAGCCAUCUGCCUAAAUUGACAUACCUUCAGCAUCUGCAUAAACUCAAUUAUGUUGGAGCUGUGUGGCAUUUUUCACCCUGCCGGGUUCCCUUGCCAGACAUGAUGUCGGUUAUCUGGCAAAAGCCAUUUUAUGUCGGCCACGAGGCAGGUGUUCACUGUGCAUCAUUCAUUCACCCCAUGAUGUUCUGGAAGUAAACCUUGGUUGUCUUUCGUUGGCCAGAGGAAUUGAAUGUCCGUCUGUCUGCCCAGGCUGGAGUGGCACGAUCUCAGCUCACUGCAGCCUCCACCUCCAGGGUUCAAGCGAUUCUCCUGCCUCAGCCUCCCGGGGAUCUCAAGGGCAUUUCCCUUUGCCCACCUCACCUUUUCAUAUUUGGUAAACUGUAUGCAUUUGCCUCCAGCCCAAGAUUAUAAAUAUGAACUGAUUAUGAUCUGCAUGUUCUCUCUUUGGGUUCAAGCAUUUCCUUACAGAAGAGCCACCGUGGAAGUCAUGGGUAAAUAUGUGUUGAAUUGGUAACUCCCUCUUGGAGAAUUUCUUGUGAAUUACACAGCAAUAGGGGAACUCAUUUAACUGGAGACAUAAUCUCAAUUUGUAAAGUGUGGCCCAUUUUCUAACAUUUUUAUUUUGCAUACCCUCCCCUCUCUUCUCGAUUGAUGAAACUAACAAAGAGGUUAAUAAAAGCCCAUCUCGUCAUGUACAGGGACUCAUGCCUUUAAUUCCAGUGUUUUGGGAGACUAAGGCAAGAACAUCCUGGAGGCCAGGAGUUCGACACUGUAUAACAGAUAUAUCUGACAGCAGUAACUCAAGCACACCCUAAGAAUGACCCUGUGGUCUAAGAAGAGUGUUGGUUCAGCGUUCCAAACGAAGAAAUCCAGGAGUGGCCAACCUGGAGGUUUCUGAACCCCUGGCCUGUUCCUUGGAAUGAGGCCCUUUGUUUUGAGCUAGGCGGAGGGUGAUAAGUGAAAAUACUAUAUAAACUGCAUGCUUCUUUCAAAUGAUAGUGGUUUUUUUGUCCAGCCUGCCGCUCCUGGACUGCCCUGUAUCUAAGUCCUCAAUAAACCCUAUGUCUCAUUUUC